GGAGACACGUGGUCGCCGAGCGGGCCACGACCUUGAGGCGCCGCUUCCUCCCGGCCCGGGGUUCUCCCGCGGCUGGAUAAGGGUGAUCCGGGCGCCUCGUUCUGCCCCCGUCUUCACAGCUCGGGGCUGGAGGGGCCUAGGGGAGACCCACCCGGAGACCCUGCGGCCCCGCGCCGGCCUCUUUCCCAACCCUUCGGCGGCCGCGCGCUGGCCGGGGAGCCGUUGGGGAGGCCCUGGCGGCCGCGCAGCAGGUGCAGGGGCGCAGAGCCCGGGCUCGCCUUGGUACAGACGAGCGGGCCCCGGCCUUGGCGCCUUCAGUUUCCUUCCAGUUUUUAUUUUCGCUGUGUCUACAGAGCAGAUGACACCAAUUUGGAAACCCGCGAGAGUGGGUAGAGCUAAGAUAGUCUUGCUGUAGUAGCUGUGAUAUUAGAUGCUCGGCCAUGACUUAGAGGUGUUUAUUUAAGGACUGUGAAUGACUCGGUGAUUUCGGAAAAGCUUGGCUUAGAUGAACGGACAUACACAGGGGAGACAGCCCUAAGAUUGUCACUGCUGUUCCAAGGGCACACGCAGAGGGAUUUGGAAUUCCUGGAGAGUUGCCUUUGUGAGAAGCUGGAAAUAUUUCUUUCAAUUCCAUCUCUUAGUUUUCCAUAGGAACAUCAAGAAAUCAUGAACAACUUUGGUAAUGAAGAGUUUGACUGCCACUUCCUCGAUGAAGGUUUUACUGCCAAGGACAUUCUGGACCAGAAAAUUAAUGAAGUUUCUUCUUCUGAUGAUAAGGAUGCCUUCUAUGUGGCAGACCUGGGAGACAUUCUAAAGAAACAUCUGAGGUGGUUAAAAGCUCUCCCUCGUGUCACCCCCUUUUAUGCAGUCAAAUGUAAUGAUAGCAAAGCCAUCGUGAAGACCCUUGCUGCUACCGGGACAGGAUUUGACUGUGCUAGCAAGACUGAAAUACAGUUGGUGCAGAGUCUGGGGGUGCCUCCAGAGAGGAUUAUCUAUGCAAAUCCUUGUAAACAAGUAUCUCAAAUUAAGUAUGCUGCUAAUAAUGGAGUCCAGAUGAUGACUUUUGAUAGUGAAGUUGAGUUGAUGAAAGUUGCCAGAGCACAUCCCAAAGCAAAGUUGGUUUUGCGGAUUGCCACUGAUGAUUCCAAAGCAGUCUGUCGUCUCAGUGUGAAAUUCGGUGCCACGCUCAGAACCAGCAGGCUCCUUUUGGAACGGGCGAAAGAGCUAAAUAUCGAUGUUGUUGGUGUCAGCUUCCAUGUAGGAAGCGGCUGUACCGAUCCUGAGACCUUCGUGCAGGCAAUCUCUGAUGCCCGCUGUGUUUUUGACAUGGGGGCUGAGGUUGGUUUCAGCAUGUAUCUGCUUGAUAUUGGCGGUGGCUUUCCUGGAUCUGAGGAUGUGAAACUUAAAUUUGAAGAGAUCACCGGCGUAAUCAACCCAGCGUUGGACAAAUACUUUCCGUCAGACUCUGGAGUGAGAAUCAUAGCUGAGCCCGGCAGAUACUAUGUUGCAUCAGCUUUCACGCUUGCAGUUAAUAUCAUUGCCAAGAAAAUUGUAUUAAAGGAACAGACGGGCUCUGAUGACGAAGAUGAGUCGAGUGAGCAGACCUUUAUGUAUUAUGUGAAUGAUGGCGUCUAUGGAUCAUUUAAUUGCAUACUCUAUGACCACGCACAUGUAAAGCCCCUUCUGCAAAAGAGACCUAAACCAGAUGAGAAGUAUUAUUCAUCCAGCAUAUGGGGACCAACAUGUGAUGGCCUCGAUCGGAUUGUUGAGCGCUGUGACCUGCCUGAAAUGCAUGUGGGUGAUUGGAUGCUCUUUGAAAACAUGGGCGCUUACACUGUUGCUGCUGCCUCUACGUUCAAUGGCUUCCAGAGGCCGACGAUCUACUAUGUGAUGUCAGGGCCUGCGUGGCAACUCAUGCAGCAAUUCCAGAACCCCGACUUCCCACCCGAAGUAGAGGAACAGGAUGCCAGCACCCUGCCUGUGUCUUGUGCCUGGGAGAGUGGGAUGAAACGCCACAGAGCAGCCUGUGCUUCGGCUAGUAUUAAUGUGUAGAUAGCACUCUGGUAGCUGUUAACUGCAAGUUUAGCUUGAAUUAAGGGAUUUGGGGGGACCAUGUAACUUAAUUACUGCUAGUUUUGAAAUGUCUUUGUAAGAGUAGGGUCGCCAUGAUGCAGCCAUAUGGAAGACUAGGAUAUGGGUCACACUUAUCUGUGUUCCUAUGGAAACUAUUUGAAUAUUUGUUUUAUAUGGAUUUUUAUUCACUCUUCAGACACGCUACUCAAGAGUGCCCCUCAGCUGCUGAACAAGCAUUUGUAGCUUGUACAAUGGCAGAAUGGGCCAAAAGCUUAGUGUUGUGACCUGUUUUUAAAAUAAAGUAUCUUGAAAUAAUUAGGCAUUGGGACGUUUUUAUGGUGUGUUCAUUCCAGACAGUUCACGAAUCCCGUAUAGCUCGCUCUGAUUCUCAGAGAACAAUGAGUGGGUCCACCCACACACAGGUAGGAGGACAGGUGAGACGGAAGCCCCAUCCUCCCAUGUGGACGGUGCACAUCUGCUCAGCCCACCCCACAUGUCCAGAGUUGGCUGCAAACUCCUUGUCCAGAGCCUCUGGUGGUGGGACCUACUUAAGUCUGACGGACCUGUCCUGUCCAGGCCAGUGCCCAGGGAAGGUGUGGGAGGCCCUUUGAGCCUGGCCUGCAGAGACCAUCCGUGUCCCCUCCCACCUUCAUGCCUGUGAGAAGUUAGGAAUGUAUACGGUACCACAUUUGGCAGUCAGCUUAUUUUAAUAAAUUCAGCAACAGCAAGUCCCUA